AAAGCUGGUGACGCAGCGCGCAGAGGCAUCGCCCGGCUAAGCUUGGCCCUGGCAGAUGGGUCGCAGGAACAGGUAUGCUUCCUUCGUGCAGCCUCUGGCUCGGGGAACCUGGGAGCCUGCUCCAAACUCUGGUGUAUCUUUUCCGGGCAGAGCCUGGGAAGUGGGGGUUGGCUGUGAGCUAAGCCAAAGGCACAGGGAUCUUGGUCCAAAAAGCCCCAUGGCGCUCACCUUGGUUUAGAGGCUAGACCAUUGAGCUGAGAAGUUUUGACAGCCAUGGAAAAGCUGGGGAUAAGUCACCUGGGGUUUUACGUUUACCCUGUGUCUAUUUUAUUAGAGUGCCUUUUACUUAUUGUCCCUUCUUCUUAGUUGAAAUUAAUGGCCUGCUUCACUGGGGCUAAGAUGUUUGAACAUUAGCAGAAGGUCCUGGCUGCAUAGCCUUGCCUUGUCUUCCCAGUUAGGAUGUAAGGACUCUUAAAGUUCCCUAAGAAAUGCAAAUAUUUUAGCAUGGCAAAAUUCUAGGCCAACUACAACUGUAAGUUUCGUAUUUCUCCUAAGUGGUUCUCAUGCCUGACUUCUGGAGCAAGGAGUCAGGUCUCCCAGGGGCUCUAGAAGGGUUCAGCUGUUCAGAAUAAAUGGUUCCUGGGGACUCUAAAAUAGCAGCAACUGUCUGCCCAGGUCAUGAGAAGACCCCUCUCUGCAGGACAUCCUAGCCCUACAACCCAUCCCAAUUAUGUUGAAAUUAGAUUCACAAAUGGCAAUAAGUCUUCUAUAUGUUGGGCUGUCGAUUUGGAGAAAACUAGUUUAAUCUUUACUUAACUUUGGGUGGCUCAACAGGAGACUCGGGCCGCUCAGGCUCUCAAUCACGUCUGGCCAGUUCUAUUAUCAGGUUUCGAAUCUGUAUCUCCAAAAUCUCUGAGGUGAUGGGAUAUUUCAAGCCCUCUAAAAUAAAUAAAUAUAUGCUGGGAAUUUUGAGAACAUGAAUUUGUUUAUUCUGAAAUGGUCCAUGUUCCUGCUUUGGGAGUUGAUGGAAAAUGCCACUUGAGUGUUUUCAUUUGAUGCUGCCACCUUAGGGUUUUAUAGAUUCAGUUCCAGAAACUCAAGGCAUUUAUCUCUUUGGGCUGCUUGUCCUUGCCUGAGCUGAAGCCUGAUGCCUCCCAUAAGUUGGUAUGGCUUUGAAAAUGGGUCACUACAGCAGAGGCAUGGGCUUAUCAAGCAAUAUGUUCAGCUAUGAAAUUUGAAGAGGGAGAUAAUCUGAAAAUAAAUGACAGCCACCACUUAGAUUAUGAAAUAGAAGUACUUUUUCAUAAGUGCUUAAUUAUUCAUACGGUUUUUUAUCUUUAACUAUGGAGCCAACUCAGCUCCAUAUGGACUUAAUUUUGGUUCCUGACCUCCAAGAUUCAUUGCAAGUCACACAGAUGUUGGUAUCUAACAUUGUUUUACCGAGAUAAAAUGACCUUGGUCUGGAAUGCAUUGUAUAAAAAGCUGCUUUUUUGUGUAAAGAUUAAUAGUUUGGCAUUGUUUAAAAAGCAGAAUGGUUAGUUGGGCAGUGAGGUAAUACAAUUGAAAUGUAAUUGCUACCAAUAAAUCAGUUACCCAUAUUGAUUUCUUUACUGGGAUUAAUAGAAGCCAAAGCUAGAGUUCAACUUUUUUUAAUAGGUAUAACUUAGUAUCUGUUCAUUGCUAUUUGUUAGCUAUGGUAAAUGGAACAAUGAUGGGGCCAGAAAUAUCCAUGAGGACCAUUUGAUCACAGCCUGGCAACACAGAGAAGACAGGCUGGUUUCUCUAUGUGGGCUUUCAGUGUUUCUUUGGUAGUGUCUUAUGUGGCUGUGGCUUCAACAUUCCACAAUUAUGCCUUCCAGGGUCUGAUGAUUUUGGCGUUUCCCUGCUUCCCAAUUGACCUGGCUGUGCUGUUGGCUGUUCUUGCACACUCAAGGUGGUUUUGCCAUUGGCUUCCUCCCUCAGCCUGCCUCUGGGAUUAUGCCACUGCUAUUCUUUUUUAUCUACCAUCAGCACAAUGAAAUCAUCAUUUUUGUCUUCAAGUCUUCUCAACUAGACUGAACUCCUUAAGUGCAAGAAAUACACGCUUAGUAAAUGUUUGUUGGACCAGACACUGCACCUUAUGAAAUUAAAGACCAGAACAUUCUCAUGGUAGCAUUACAGACACUGAUGGCAAAGGAGCCAGAGGAAGAGAUAGCCAUGGAGGACAGCCCCACUAUGGUUAGAGUGGACAGCCCCACUAUGGUUAGGGGUGAAAACCAGGUUUCGCCAUGUCAAGGGAGAAGGUGCUUCCCCAAAGCUCUUGGCUAUGUCACCGGUGACAUGAAAGAACUUGCCAACCAGCUUAAAGACAAACCCGUGGUGCUCCAGUUCAUUGACUGGAUUCUCCGGGGCAUAUCCCAAGUGGUGUUCGUCAACAACCCCGUCAGUGGAAUCCUGAUUCUGGUAGGACUUCUUGUUCAGAACCCCUGGUGGGCUCUCACUGGCUGGCUGGGAACAGUGGUCUCCACUCUGAUGGCCCUCUUGCUCAGCCAGGACAGGUCAUUAAUAGCAUCUGGGCUCUAUGGCUACAAUGCCACCCUGGUGGGAGUACUCAUGGCUGUCUUUUCGGACAAGGGAGACUAUUUCUGGUGGCUGUUACUCCCUGUAUGUGCUAUGUCCAUGACUUGCCCAAUUUUCUCAAGUGCAUUGAAUUCCAUGCUCAGCAAAUGGGACCUCCCCGUCUUCACCCUCCCUUUCAACAUGGCGUUGUCAAUGUACCUUUCAGCCACAGGACAUUACAAUCCAUUCUUUCCAGCCAAACUGGUCAUACCUAUAACUACAGCUCCAAAUAUCUCCUGGUCUGACCUCAGUGCCCUGGAGUUGUUGAAAUCUAUACCAGUGGGAGUUGGUCAGAUCUAUGGCUGUGAUAAUCCAUGGACAGGGGGCAUUUUCCUGGGAGCCAUCCUACUCUCCUCCCCACUCAUGUGCCUGCAUGCUGCCAUAGGAUCAUUGCUGGGCAUAGCAGCGGGACUCAGUCUUUCAGCCCCAUUUGAGGACAUCUACUUUGGACUCUGGGGUUUCAACAGCUCUCUGGCCUGCAUUGCAAUGGGAGGAAUGUUCAUGGCGCUCACCUGGCAAACCCACCUCCUGGCUCUUGGCUGUGCCCUGUUCACGGCCUAUCUUGGAGUCGGCAUGGCAAACUUUAUGGCUGAGGUUGGAUUGCCAGCUUGUACCUGGCCCUUCUGUUUGGCCACGCUAUUGUUCCUCAUCAUGACCACAAAAAAUUCCAACAUCUACAAGAUGCCCCUCAGUAAAGUUACUUAUCCUGAAGAAAACCGCAUCUUCUACCUGCAAGCCAAGAAAAGAAUGGUGGAAAGCCCUUUGUGAGAACAAGCCCCAUUUGCAGCCAUGGUCACGAGUCAUUUCUGCCUGACUGCUCCAGCUAACUUCCAGGGUCUCAGCAAACUGCUGUUUUUCACGAGUAUCAACUUUCAUACUGACGCGUCUGUAAUCUGUUCUUAUGCUCAUUUUGUAUUUUCCUUUCAACUCCAGGAAUAUCCUUGAGCAUAUGAGAGUCACAUCCAGGUGAUGUGCUCUGGUAUGGAAUUUGAAACCCCAAUGGGGCCUUGGCACUAAGACUGGAAUGUAUAUAAAGUCAAAGUGCUCCAACAGAAGGAGGAAGUGAAAACAAACUAUUAGUAUUUAUUGAUAUUCUUGGUGUUUAGCUGGCUCGAUGAUGUUAACAGUAUUAAAAAUUAAACCCCAUAAACCAACUAAGCCUUAUGGAAUUCACAGUCACAAAAUCGAAGUUAAUCCAGAAUUCUGUGAUAAGCAGCUUGGCUUUUUUUUUAAAUCAAUGCAAGUUACACAUUAUAGCCAGAAUCUGUAUCACAGAGGUGCAAGCUGACAGCAGAGCUCAGUCCCCACUUCCUGCAAACAAUGGCCUGCACCCUAUCCCUUGUGUGUGUGACAUUCUCUCAUGGGACAAUGUUGGGGUUUUUCAGACUGACAGGACUGCAAGAGGGAGAAAGGAAUUUUGUCAAUCAAAAUUAUUCUGUAUUGCAACUUUUCUCAGAGAUUGCAAAGGAUUUUUUAGGUAGAGAUUAUUUUUCCUUAUGAAAAAUGAUCUGUUUUAAAUGAGAUAAAAUAGGAGAAGUUCCUGGCUUAACCUGUUCUUACAUAUUAAAGAAAAGUUACUUACUGUAUUUAUGAAAUACUCAGCUUAGGCAUUUUUACUUUAACCCCUAAAUUGAUUUUGUAAAUGCCACAAAUGCAUAGAAUUGUUACCAACCUCCAAAGGGCUCUUUAAAAUCAUAUUUUUUAUUCAUUUGAGGAUGUCUUAUAAAGACUGAAGGCAAAGGUCAGAUUGCUUACGGGUGUUAUUUUUAUAAGUUGUUGAAUUCCUUAAUUUAAAAAAGCUCAUUAUUUUUUGCACACUCACAAUAUUCUCUCUCAGAAAUCAAUGGCAUUUGAACCACCAAAAAGAAAUAAAGGGCUGAGUGCGGUGGCUCACGCCUGUAAUCCCAGCACUUUGGGGAGCCCAGGCGGGCAGAUUGCUUGAACCCAGGAGUUCAAGACCAGCCUGGGCAGCAUGGUGAAACCCUGUAUCUACAAAAAAUACAAAAAUUAGCCAGGCAUGGUGGUGGGUGCCUGUAGUUCCAGCUACUUGGGAGGCUGAGGUGGGAAAAUGACUUGAGCCCAGGAGGAGGAGGCUGCAGUGAGCUAAGAUUGCACCACUGCACUCCAACCUGGGCGACAAGAGUGAAACUGUGUCUCUCAAAAAAAAAAAAAAACAAACAAAAACAAAAACAAAACAAAACAAAACAAAACAAAACAGGUAAGGAUUCCCCUGUUUUCCUCUCUUUAAUUUUAAAGUUAUCAGUUCCGUAAAGUCUCUGUAACCAAACAUACUGAAGACAGCAACAGAAGUCACGUUCAGGGACUGGCUCACACCUGUAAUCCCAGCACUUUGGGAGAUGGAGGUAAAAGGAUCUCUUGAGCCCAGGAGUUCAAGACCAGCUUGGGCAACAUAGCAAGACUCCAUCUCUUAAAAAAUAAAAAUAGUAACAUUAGCCAGGUGUAGCAGCACACAUCUGCAGCAGCUACUCAGGAGGCUGAGGUGGAAAGAUCGCUUGUGCACAGAAGUUCGAGGCUGCAGUGAGCUAUAUGAUCAUGUCACUGCACUCCAGCCUGUGUGACCGAGCAAGACCCUAUCUCAAAAAAAUUAAUUAAUUAAUUAAUUAAUUAAUUUAAAAAGGAAGUCAUGUUCAUUUACUUUCCACUUCAGUGUGUAUCGUGUAGUAUUUUGGAGGUUGGAAAGUGAAACGUAGGAAUCCUGAAGAUUUUUUCCACUUCUAGUUUGCAGUGCUCAGUGCACAAUAUACAUUUUGCUGAAUGAAUAAACAGAAAUAGGGAAGUAAACCUACAAAUAUUUUAGGGAGAAGCUCACUUCUUCCUUUUCUCAGGAAACCAAGCAAGCAAACAUAUCGUUCCAAUUUUAAAACCCAGUGACCAAAGCCUUUGGAACUAUGAAUUUGCAACUGUCAUAGGUUUAUGGAUAUUGCUGUGGAGAAGCUCAAUUUUCAGUGUUUGAACUGAACCCUUUCUUGUUAGGGAACGUGUGAAAGAAGAAUUGUGGGGAAAAAAAAGCAAGCAUAACCAAAGAUCAUCAGCAGUGAAGAAUCUAGGCUGUGGCUGAGAGAACCAGAGGCCUCUAAAAUGGACCCGAGUCGAUCUUCAGAACAGGGAUCUACCAUGCAGGAGCUUCUUGUGCUCACACAAAUCUGUAAAUGGGAACAUUGUACAUUGUCGAAUUUAAAUGAUAUUAAUUUUCUCAAGCUAUUUUUGUUACUAUUUUCCUAAAAUUGAAUAUUUGCAGGGAGCACUUAUACUUUUUCCUAAUGUCUGUAUAACAAAUUUCUAUGCAAGUACAUGAAUAAAUUAUGCUCACAGCUCA